AGGCCUCGGAGGCGGGGCGAUGGCCACCUCCCACCGAGUGGCGAAGCUGGUGGCCUCCAGUCUCCAGACCCCGGUAAAUCCCAUCACUGGAGCGCGGGUCGCCCAGUACGAACGCGAAGACCCCUUAAAGGCCCUGGCGGCAGCGGAGGCGAUCUUGGAGGACGAAGAGGAGGAGAAAGUGGCUCAGCCCGCUGGGGCAUCGGCUGAUUUGAACACCAGCUUUUCUGGGGUGGAUGAACAUGCACCGAUAAGCUAUGAGGACUUUGUGAACUUUCCUGAUAUUCACCACUCUAAUGAGGAGUAUUUCAAGAAAGUAGAAGAGUUGAAGGCUGCCCACAUAGAAACUAUGGCAAAAUUAGAGAAAAUGUACCAGGAUAAAUUACAUUUAAAGGAAGUUCAGCCAGUGGUCAUCAGAGAAGACUCUCUUAGUGACUCUUCCAGAUCUGUAUCAGAAAAGAACUCCUAUCACCCUGUCUCAUUAAUGACAUCAUUUUCAGAGCCUGAUUUAGGCCAGUCUUCCUCCUUGUAUGUGUCCUCCUCUGAAGAGGAGUUACCCAACCUAGAAAAAGAGUAUCCUAGGAAAAACAGAAUGAUGACCUAUGCUAAGGAGCUCAUCAACAAUAUGUGGACAGACUUUUGUGUUGAGGAUUAUAUUCGCUGUAAAGAUACUGGCUUCCAUGCAGCUGAAAAAAGAAGGAAGAAACGAAAAGAAUGGGUGCCCACAAUUACAGUACCGGAGCCUUUUCAAAUGAUGAUAAGAGAACAGAAGAAAAAAGAAGAGUCCAUGAAAUCUAAAUCAGAUAUCGAAAUGGUACAUAAAGCGCUCAAAAAACAAGAAGAGGAUCCAGAGUAUAAGAAGAAAUUCCGAGCCAAUCCAGUUCCUGCAUCUGUCUUUCUCCCCCUUUACCAUGAUUUAGUCAAGCAAAAAGAAGAACGGAGAAGGUCUCUGAAGGAGAAAAGCAAAGAAGCUCUUUUGGCCUCACAAAAGCCAUUUAAAUUUAUAGCAAGGGAGGAACAGAAGCGAGCAGCCCGGGAAAAGCAGCUGAGAGACUUUCUUAAGUAUAAAAAGAAAACAAAUCGAUUUAAAGCCAGACCCAUUCCUCGAUCUACUUAUGGUUCAACUACCAAUGACAAGUUAAAAGAAGAAGAGCUCUAUCGAAACCUUAGGACACAGCUGAGAGCCCAGGAGCAUUUACAGAACUCAUCUCCUCUGCCUUGUAGGUCAGCUUGUGGAUGCAGGAACCCCAGGUGUCCUGAACAGGCUGUAAAGUUGAAGUGUAAACACAAGGUUAGGUGCCCAACUCCUGAUUUUGAGGACCUUCCUGAGAGAUACCAGAAACACCUCUCAGAACACAAGUCUCCAAAACUCUUAACAGUGUGUAAACCAUUUGAUCUUCAUGCAUCUCCACAUGCAUCUAUUAAAAGAGAAAAAAUUUUGGCAGACAUCGAAGCAGAUGAAGAAAAUUUAAAAGAAACACGUUGGCCUUAUUUGUCUCCAAGGCGUAAGUCACCAGUAAGAUGUGCAGGUGUAAACCCUGUGCCUUGUAACUGCAACCCUCCCGUGCCCACGGUAUCUUCCAGAGGACGAGAACAAGCCGUAAGGAGAUCACUUGAGGAAAAGAAAAUGUUGGAAGAAGAGAGAAAUCGGAUCCUAACUAAACAGAAGCAAAGAAUGAAAGAAUUGCAGAAACUCCUGACAACCCGGGCUAAGGCUUAUGACUCACAUCAAAGUUUAGCUCAAAUAUCUAAAUCCAGAGUAAAAUGUCUCAGAAAGAGCGAAAAGGAAAGGAUGAGAGAAUACCAACGAGAACUAGAAGAAAGAGAAGAAAAAUUAAAAAAGAGGCCACUGCUAUUUGAAAGAGUUGCUCAGAAAAAUGCAAGAAUGGCAGCAGAAAAGCAUUAUUCUAAUACCCUAAAAGCACUAGGAAUAUCUGAUGAGUUUGUUUCAAAGAAAGGCCAAAGUGGAAAAGUACUUGAGUACUUCAACAAUCAAGAGACGAAAAGUGUCACUGAAGACAAAGAAAGCUUUAAUGAAGAAGAAAAAAUAGAAGAAAGAGAGAAUGGGGAAGAAAAUUAUUUUAUUGAUACCAACAGCCAGGAUUCUUACAAGGAAAAAGAUGAAGCCAAUGAGGAAAGUGAAGAAGAGAAAUCUGUUGAAGAAUCACACUGAAUCAUCAAGGUCUCCUCUCUAUGCCCUUGCUGUUGUUUGCAGCGUCAGGGUGUCAGCAGCCGCAUUUGUGUUUAGAACAUCUGUGGGGACGCUUCUGAUAUGUGCAGGGCUGUUGAUCAAAGUCAUCUGUAGCCUGAAAAGCCUGAAUCCAGCUGAUUGGUCAUUUGAUCAGUUAGAGUAAGGCUUUGCCUAUUCAGUUUUAAAAAUCAUUGUGUAUUAUCUGUUUGCAACUAUGAUUUUGUAUUUUUAAAAAGUGAGAACCACAGCUGUCACAAACUGAUUAGUUAUAAAAAUAUACAUUAUUUCAUUAAUUUUACUGGAAAAAAUGGCUUAGUAUUGAAAGGAGAGAGAAGUAUUGGUCUUUGGUGGUUUACUUUUUAAAAAUUUUGGAAAGUGUGAAUCAAUAACUAUUUUUAAUUAUACUAUUUGCCCAUUCUUUUUCUCUGCAGUGCAUUUCACAGAAUAAAUCCUCUAACUUGUUUUGCUGCUCUGAGCCAUUUUUAAAAGUAUAGAAAAAACGCCGGGUAUGGUGGCUCAUGCCUGUAAUCCCAGCAUUUUGGGAGGCCGAGACGGGUGGAUCACGAGGUCAGGAGAUCGAGACCAUCCUGGCUAACACGAUGAAACCCCGUCUCUACUAAAAAUACAAAAAAUUAGCCAGGCGUGGUGGUGGGCGCCUGUAGUCCCAGCUACUUGGGAGGCAGAGGCAGGAGAAUGGCAUGAACCCAGGAGGCAGAGCUUGCAGUGAGCCGAGAUCGCGCCACUGCACUCCAGCUUGGGCAACAGAGCGAGACUCCGUCUCCAAAAAAAAAAAAAAAGUAUAGAAAAAAAUGGAUACUUGCAAAUUUACAUUUAUUUUUGCACUGAGAGUUUACUGUUAAAUUGUCUACACCAUCAUCCCUUUUUCUUUUUAUCCUUAGUUCUAGUCCAAAUUAUUUUUGAUUUGUAAAUUAUUAGGAAAGUUUUUAUACUAGUUUUUUUAACCCUAUGUAUUAUUACAGAUGGAAGUAAUUAUGGCAUGUGUGAGUUAUAAUCUAAAUUAGGGGCAAGUAUCCCUUUUUUUAUAUGAUGAAAUUGUGCAUAAUAACUUGGCUAGGGCAAGUCUCCAAAGUAAUUCAGAUUUAACUCUUCACUGCUAGACCCAGUUGUGUUCAACUUUUUACAUAUUAUUGCCAACACACUUUAUCUCUCUGUGUACAGUGUUAAUCUGAUUUUAUAAAUCUAUAUUUUUUUCUUUAAGCAAAUUUUUGUUUUAAAAUUUGAAGCCAAUCAUAAAGAUAAUAUAGCAUAAGACAUUUUCUUUUCUAAAAACAAUCAGCAUCAUUUUAAAAGGAUGAACUAAUACAGGUGUAUGUAAUAGCAGUGUUUCCAAACUGGCAAUUUAUGCUUUAAAUUUAAAAAUAAGGUCAUUUUUCUCCAUCAGGGGCAAAUGUUUACUUGUAAUUUUCUUCCUACAGUUCGUGUUAAAUUACUUUUUACUAUUAUUAUAUUGUAAACUCCUUGGGAUUUGGCACCAUUUAAAAAUUCAUCUUUGUAUUCCCUUAAUAUUUGGAACAGUAUUGUACAUAUGGUAGGUACUUAAUAAAGGUUUGAAUGAGUGUGUAGAUGAA